GUUCUUCCUUCGCAGUCGUUCCCUGCCAGCCGCGCGCCGCCUCCAGGUGCACUCCAGGAGCAGCCGCGCCGCUGCUCACCCGCCCUGUAGUCCGCUCCCCCCAGGGCCGUCCCCGUUUUAAGAAAUGGGGUGAUGGGGCGUCCCUACCCGGCGCCUGCAGGGGCUCCUGGGGAGCGCGCCGGUGGCUCGCUGCUCCCGGGUGGGGCGCGGGGCUGGCGCUCGAGGGUGCCGUGGCCCAGGCGGGGCUGCAGCGAGUGUGUUCCCCGUUCCGCGCGCGUGAAGCGUGGGAGCGAAGCCUCGGGGGAGGGCGGGAGCGCGGCUGAGCUCACUGUGAACACCCGGCUGGGUAGUCCCGCGAGCAGGGGAGGGGCCGGAACCGAUGUGUAUGCGGAGAGGUCGCAGUCAUUGCUGGCAGGAUGUACACGCUGCUGUCGGGCUUGUACAAGUACAUGUUUCAGAAGGACGAGUACUGCAUCCUGAUCCUGGGCCUGGACAAUGCUGGGAAGACGACCUUCCUGGAGCAGUCGAAAACCCGAUUUAACAAGAACUACAAGGGGAUGAGUCUAUCCAAAAUCACCACCACCGUGGGCCUAAACAUCGGCACUGUGGAUGUGGGAAAGGCUCGGCUCAUGUUCUGGGACUUAGGAGGGCAGGAAGAGCUGCAGUCUUUGUGGGACAAGUAUUAUGCGGAGUGUCACGGCGUCAUCUACGUCAUUGACUCCACCGACGAGGAGAGGCUGGCUGAGUCCAAGCAGGCGUUUGAGAAGGUGGUGACCAGCGAGGCGCUGUGCGGUGUCCCCGUCUUGGUGCUGGCCAACAAGCAGGAUGUGGAGACGUGCCUCUCAAUCCCUGACAUCAAGACGGCCUUCAGCGACUGCACCAGCAAGAUCGGCAGGCGAGAUUGCCUGACCCAGGCCUGCUCGGCCCUCACAGGCAAAGGGGUGCGCGAGGGCAUCGAGUGGAUGGUGAAGUGUGUCGUGCGGAAUGUGCACCGGCCGCCGCGGCAGAGGGACAUCACGUAGGCGCAGCCGCGCUGCCGUCGGGACGGCUGGUCCCCUGGUGCUGGAGGAGUGGCCUCCUGUUGGCUCCCAUGCUGCUGAUCUGGGGGGUGGGUUUGCUUUGCUUUGGGGUUCUUCUAUUUACUUUGUUUUCUCGAAGACAAACUUUCCUCUAUGUCUGGAAAAGCGUAGGCAUCCGGAGGCUUUGGAGGGGAGUCUGGCAGCCCGGCUGGCCCAGGCCCUGCAGCGGCAGCCUUUCCACAGGGCGCAGCGGCGGCCUUUCGAGGCCCUUUCUGGGGGGUCUGAGGGAGACCUGGUUGGGAAUUGGGGCUCCAGUGCUCAGGCUGGCUUGGGCUGCAUGAGGACAGCCCUGUGGGACCCUCGGGAGACCCCGUGGCUGUCUCCGCCCCAUCGAGGAGGAGGCCCGUCAGCCAUGGCUGCCAUCUGGCUUCUGCCCUGUGACCCCGUGACCCCGUGACCCCGGAAGUGGUCUGGGGCUGAUCUUGCCUUGAGGAAGACCCAGGCCAUGUUCCCAAAGGCCAGCGGGGGCCCUGGAUUGUGAUGCAGCCUCGGGACAGGGCUGAGGCCUGCGGGGGAAGACCUAUACCCCACGCCUGGGCCUGGCUUCACCUCACCCUAAUCCCCCGGGAGGGAGCUGACUGAUGCAAAAAGCUGAGGGGGCCUGCUGGGAGUGGCUGUUUUUAUGCCCCAGCCCCGCAAGUUGGGGAGUGUUUGUGGGGGUCCAGAGCCCUCCCCCAGCCAGGAGAGAACCUCCCGGAGGGGUUCUCUGUGGGGCCCUGUGUCCCCUGCUCGGGAGUAAGGCUGGUCCUGGGGUCCUCCCUGCACGGACCCCACUGGGCCUGCCGAGUGCUGUGUUCUUCCUCAGUCUGGCUGUGGGCAGGAGCGGCCUGCCCAGUGUCACCCAGGGUGAGUGCAAAAUAAAGACGGCGAGUGUGGCUCUGUCCAUCCCUUCCCUCCUGGAGGGUGGAGGCUCCUGGCUGUUGGACACGGUGAUGGUGUUACUGGGCUGCUCAGGGGCUGGUGGGCAGGUGAGGGGCUCCCCAGGUGGGCCUGGAGAGUCCAGGCACUCCCUUCCUGCGGAUGUGGGAAGGACAUGGGGUCCUGGGAGGAGCUGCUGGGAAGGGGCAUGAGUCAGGGUGGGGGUGGCGCAGCAGCUGCGGGGCUGUGACUCACAGGAGUCGGGCCCUGGAAGUCCCCGCGUCCUCUCCAGGGGACCCUGUGUGUGUUCUGCAGGUUGGUUCCCAGGACCUGGGGGGGACCUCCAGCCCCGGGAACCUGGCCGUGCUGGGGAGGCGAGUGGCUGGUGCAGCCCCCCGGUUGCUCUGGGUGCAUCGGGAGGCUUCAGAGCCUGCCCCAGAGAGGGAGAAGCUUCACUUCCCGGAAAGCAUGGGAGGCCUGGAGGAGGUCUUUGGCAGGUCCCCUCUCGGGAAAUCCCCUGUGAGUUGGGAGUGGGAGGAAUUCAUAAGUGGGGGGUUAGUGUGGGCCCCGGCGACUAGGGCUGGCCUGAGCCCCAUCCUGUUCUUCCAGCAAUGAUACCCUCCCAGGCCCUGACCCUCGCUGAGCUUCAGGGGCCCCUGCCACGUGCCACAGCCACUGGGGGCAGAGGUGGCACUCCCCACUGAUCCUCCCAGGGAGGGUCUGUCUGAGGUAGGGGAAGCCCCGGGCAGCAGUUCUGAUGGCAGGCAGCCUGAGGGAUCUGGGCACAGCGGGCGGCUCAGGUGUCCCCGGCUGCCCUCCCAGUAGCUGUGCAACUACAACCAGUUUUAUGAAAAAGCUUUAUAAAAAUAAGCUUUAAGAAA